AGAAGUCUGUCCGCGAGCUGUCAGCGCGGGCGGGAACGCCGCGGGGCGCGGGGUGGGCGCGGCCGACCUGGUCCCUGAGCCGGCCGGCGACCCCGGACCUCCCGCGCGCCCCGCACCCGACCGGCUCAGCCGGCCGGCAGCGUAACACGCCCUACGCUCGCUUGCUCGCCGGCCUCAGGGCAGGCAGGCGGGCGCGGGAGACCCCGCCGGGGCCGAGACUUGGGGCGGGCGACGAGGACCAGGUUACGGCCUCCUCGCCAUGUCCUCGGCCUGCGACGCGGGCGACCACUACCCCCUGCACCUCCUAGUCUGGAAAAACGACUACCGGCAGCUCGAGAAGGAGCUGCAGGGCCAGAAUGUGGAGGCUGUGGACCCACGAGGUCGAACAUUAUUGCAUCUUGCUGUUUCCUUGGGACAUUUGGAAUCUGCUCGAGUCUUACUCCGACAUAAAGCAGAUGUGACAAAAGAAAAUCGCCAGGGAUGGACAGUUUUACAUGAGGCUGUGAGCACUGGCGAUCCUGAGAUGGUGUACACAGUUCUCCAACAUCGAGACUACCACAACACAUCCAUGGCCCUUGAGGGAGUUCCUGAGCUGCUCCAAAAAAUUCUCGAGGCUCCGGAUUUCUAUGUGCAGAUGAAAUGGGAAUUCACCAGCUGGGUGCCCUUGGUUUCUAGAAUAUGCCCAAAUGAUGUCUGUCGCAUCUGGAAAAGUGGUGCCAAACUGCGCGUCGAUAUCACAUUGCUGGGAUUUGAAAACAUGAGCUGGAUAAGAGGGAGGCGUAGUUUUAUAUUUAAGGGAGAAGACAACUGGGCGGAGUUAAUGGAAGUCAACCAUGAUGACAAAGUGGUCACCACCGAACGCUUCGACCUUUCCCAAGAAAUGGAGCGCCUCACUCUGGACUUGAUGAAGCCAAAAAGCAGGGAAGUUGAGCGGCGGCUCACAAGCCCUGUCAUUAACACCAGCCUCGAUACUAAAAAUAUUGCUUUUGAAAGAACUAAAUCCGGAUUCUGGGGCUGGAGGACAGAUAAAGCAGAAGUUGUUAAUGGUUACGAAGCAAAGGUUUACACAGUAAACAAUGUGAAUGUGAUCACCAAAAUACGCACAGAACAUCUGACCGAGGAGGAAAAAAAGAGAUAUAAAGCAGACAGGAACCCGCUGGAAUCUUUGCUGGGAACUGUGGAACACCAAUUUGGUGCACAAGGGCAGGACCUCACCACGGAAUGUGCUACUGCAAACAACCCCACAGCCAUCACGCCUGAUGAGUACUUCAAUGAAGAGUUUGAUCUGAAAGACAGGGACAUUGGAAGGCCGAAAGAGCUGACGAUUAGAACACAGAAGUUUAAAGCAAUGUUGUGGAUGUGUGAAGAGUUUCCCCUCUCUCUGGUGGAGCAGGUCAUUCCCAUCAUUGACCUAAUGGCUCGAACGAGUGCUCAUUUUGCAAGACUGAGAGAUUUCAUCAAAUUGGAAUUCCCACCUGGAUUUCCUGUCAAAAUAGAAAUUCCCUUGUUUCAUGUCUUAAAUGCACGGAUUACAUUUGGAAAUGUUAAUGGCUGUAGCACUGCCGAAGAAUCUGUAUCUCAAAAUGUGGAAGGGACCCAGGCUGAUUCAGCUUCCCACAUCACAAACUUUGAGGUUGAUCAAUCUGUGUUUGAAAUUCCCGAAUCUUACUAUGUUCAAGACAAUGGCAGAAAUGUGCAUUUGCAAGAUGAAGAUUACGAGAUAAUGCAGUUUGCCAUCCAGCAAAGUCUGCUGGAGUCCAGCAGGAGCCAGGAACUUUCAGGACCAGCUUCGAAUGGAGGGAUCAGCCAGACAAACACCUAUGACGCCCAGUAUGAGAGGGCCAUCCAGGAGAGCCUCCUCACCAGCACAGAAGGCCUGUGCCCCAGCGCCCUGAGCGAGACAAGCCGUUUUGAUAAUGACUUGCAGCUAGCCAUGGAGCUCUCUGCCAAAGAGCUGGAGGAAUGGGAGCUCCGGCUCCAGGAGGAAGAGGCUGAGCUCCAGCAAGUCUUACAGCUGUCACUCACUGACAAAUAGACCUUUCAGCCUGUGAGCCUCUGCACAAAGCAGAGGCUGUGGGCUGUCACAGAUGCUGUGUCAACCAGGGCCCUAGGGCUAAGGGCCUGCACCUUGCGUGCAUGCAGCAGGCAACAACUGCCCCUUCUUUAUGCAGAGGUGCAGAACCAGGGACUCCUGGGCCCAUCCAGGCUGCUCCCUGGGGUGGAGAAGGGACCAGGGAUUGCAGGCCCCAUCUCCAGGCUAAGGGGAGGAGAGCAUCAUCACUUUCCAUUAGCUGUAUUGGCUUGCAGGUCACAUUUUUACUACCAGCUUUAGACAAAACCCCAAUCCCCGCAGGUUUGUAGAUAAAUUUUUAUCAAGGAGUGAUAACAAGACAAGUUAUUGCAGAGUCAGGGUGCUUUUAUAUAUAAGAGCAGCAGCCGCCUUUGUAAAGUGUGAUCUAUGAGAAUUGGAGACACUUCUUUACUGUUCACCAAAGAAAUGGGUAAUCUGUGCUGAUCUCCUUAUUUUUACCUUUUUACAGGGUUUCUAGGACAUUGUCAUUAUUCUUCCUCCAUCUAUCUGAUUCCAUUCCUUCCACACCCAGCUAAAGUUAGAGGAGAUACAUAUAGAAUCUAUUUUAGAUUAUUGUUAACUAUUUGCAUCAAAUUAAGAUACACAAAUGGCCAUGGAUGUUGCCUUAGCCUUAAACAUUACUAAUAGUUUCACAUCACCUCACUGCACGCAUCGAAGGAUCUGAUUUGAAUUUGUAAAGGCAAUUCUUUUGAGAGCAGGAUUCUCCAGGCUAAAUCAAAGGCAGCUAAUCCUGUCCCUGAAGGAGCAGCUAGGGGAACCUGAGGCUUGUUCUUGAAGUGGGCAAGCUGGCCAAAAUAUUGGAACACACAGAACCAAACCAGGUGUGUUCUACACCUGCAUGAGUGAAGGAUUUCCACGUAGACACCUAGGAAGAGCCCGCAUGCCCUAGACUCACUCCAGAGGAAGGAUUGAUUUGCAACCAGAAAGGGAGCUGAAAACCACGGAGCUCCAUGGCUCUUCAUUCAAAAGGGAAAAUAAUGAUUCCACGUUGCUUUUUAGAGUUCAAAUCAACAUCUUUCUGGAUAAAUCUAUUUUUUAACAAUCUUUUUAUUAUUUGUAAAAGAUAUAAAAACAACUCCCAUCAGUAGCAAUACAAGGUUAUACAUUUUAACCAGAUUUUCUCAGGCCUUUUUUGGAUACCUUUAGUAGUUAACUCUCUUUUGUCAAACCCUCUUGUAUAUAACCAUCGCACAACAUACAGAACCCUGGGGAAUACAGCCAAGGGCACUGCUCACUGUGGCCCGUGUAUUCAUUCCCACAGGCUGCACUGAAAUAACCUGGUAAACAACACCCUCCUCCAUUUUGCGUCUAUUUCUUCUAUUGUGCUUCUUUGGGGAUAGGAAGAGAAACAUAACUACUGUUCCAGGUAACGUCUGUAUCAUACAGUUAGUGUUGCCAGUGAAACGUUCCCAGAUACAAAGAAUUGUGCUUUUAAUUCCAUUUCACAAUCUGUUUUGUUUUUUUUUUUUGUCAUUGUCUGACCAAAAUUCCUUCUGCACAUGAGGCCAGUAUAGGCAACGUCACAUUUGUUUGUUUCAAAUAUGCAGUGUGGUAUUUUGUUUACUUUGCAUUUACCGUGAGCAAAGAUACUUCUUGGAAUGGCUGCAGUGAGGCCGUGUCAUUGGCUCACAAAAGUGACUCAUAGGUAAUUUCUGUGUUUGCAUUCCACUGCUCUGCUCCCUAAGGUCCUUGACUUUCUCCCCAGGAAUUCACUUAAAAAGGGACUGAGCAUUGUGUCAACCUGUUGCAGUGUUUUUCAUAUAUGUGUUCACUCUAAAAAUGCAAAUAAAGACUGCUUCCUUAGAGGGUGCUCAUACAAAAUUCCAGUCUUUGAGUCUUUUUCCUUUUCAGUUUUUUCUAGUCACUGGAUGUACCCACACUUCCUGUUACGUAUGUCAGUAGAACAUUAGAAUGCCUCACUUCGCUCAGUUCAUCACUGCAAAGGUGGCAUGCUCCUCCCAGCCUUCCUGCCCAGGUUAACAAGCCCCAUGCUGCUUGUUUCAAAUGGCAACUAAAAGCAAGCCAGUGUUGGGCUGUUCUGACACCUCUGUGGUCCUCCUGGAGGGGAACUGGCUCUUGUGGGGUAAGGGAAGCCCAGCCAACAUCAAAGCUCUGCAUCAAUGCUAUCCCUUGAAGCCAACUGCUUUGUGAG